GUCUUGUCGGCUCCUGUGUGUAGGAGGGAUUUCGGCCUGAGAGCGGGCCGAGGAGAUUGGCGACGGUGUCGCCCGUGUUUUCGUUGGCGGGUGCCUGGGCUGGUGGGAACAGCCGCCCGAAGGAAGCACCAUGAUUUCGGCCGCGCAGUUGUUGGAUGAGUUAAUGGGCCGGGACCGAAACCUAGCCCCGGACGAGAAGCGCAGCAACGUGCGGUGGGACCACGAGAGCGUUUGUAAAUAUUAUCUCUGUGGUUUUUGUCCUGCGGAAUUGUUCACAAAUACACGUUCUGAUCUUGGUCCGUGUGAAAAAAUUCAUGAUGAAAAUCUACGAAAACAGUAUGAGAAGAGCUCUCGUUUCAUGAAAGUUGGCUAUGAGAGAGAUUUUUUGCGAUACUUACAGAGCUUACUUGCAGAAGUAGAACGUAGGAUCAGACGAGGCCAUGCUCGUUUGGCAUUAUCUCAAAACCAGCAGUCUUCUGGGGCCGCUGGCCCAACAGGCAAAAAUGAAGAAAAAAUUCAGGUUCUAACAGACAAAAUUGAUGUACUUCUGCAACAGAUUGAAGAAUUAGGGUCUGAAGGAAAAGUAGAAGAAGCCCAGGGGAUGAUGAAAUUAGUUGAGCAAUUAAAAGAAGAGAGAGAACUGCUAAGGUCCACAACGUCGACAAUUGAAAGCUUUGCUGCACAAGAAAAACAAAUGGAAGUUUGUGAAGUAUGUGGAGCCUUUUUAAUAGUAGGAGAUGCCCAGUCCCGGGUAGAUGACCAUUUGAUGGGAAAACAACACAUGGGCUAUGCCAAAAUUAAAGCUACUGUAGAAGAAUUAAAAGAAAAGUUAAGGAAAAGAACCGAAGAACCUGAUCGUGAUGAGCGUCUAAAAAAGGAGAAGCAAGAAAGAGAAGAAAGAGAAAAAGAACGGGAGAGAGAAAGGGAAGAAAGAGAAAGGAAAAGACGAAGGGAAGAGGAAGAAAGAGAAAAAGAAAGGGCUCGUGACAGAGAAAGAAGAAAGAGAAGUCGUUCACGAAGUAGACACUCAAGCCGAACAUCAGACAGAAGAUGCAGCAGGUCUCGGGACCACAAAAGGUCACGAAGUAGAGAAAGAAGGCGGAGCAGAAGUAGAGAUCGACGAAGAAGCAGAAGCCAUGAUCGAUCAGAAAGAAAACACAGAUCUCGAAGUCGGGAUCGAAGAAGAUCAAAAAGCCGGGAUCGAAAGUCAUAUAAGCACAGGAGCAAAAGUCGGGACAGAGAACAAGAUAGAAAAUCCAAGGAGAAAGAAAAGAGGGGAUCUGAUGAUAAAAAAAGUAGUGUGAAGUCCGGUAGUCGAGAAAAGCAGAGUGAAGACACAAACACUGAAUCGAAGGAAAGUGAUACUAAGAAUGAGGUCAAUGGGACCAGUGAAGACAUUAAAUCUGAAGGUGACACUCAGUCCAAUUAAAACUGAUCUGAUAAGACCUCAGAUCAGACAGAGGUAAGUGUAUUGUUUCUCACUUUGAUUAGGGCUUUUUGUUACUGUUUGACAGUGCAGCGUAAGUAUGCACAGAUGAAGAUGGAACUAAGCCGAGUAAGAAGACAUACAAAAGCCUCUUCUGAAGGAAAAGACAGUGUAGUCCUGCAAAACAUUUUGAGGUACAUUGUUUUGUCUCAGCUAUUUUGUAGCAGACUCGUGCCCCCAUUAGUGUGCCUCUUUGGAAAUUAUCGCCCACAUUUGUAAUAUAGUCGCCAUUGAAAAGUUAAUUAUCCUUUUUUUAGGGAUUUUGAUGUCAUUUCUUUUUUUUUUUUAAUAAAAAGGUUGAACUGUUUUUUUUUUUCUUUUUGGUAUUAAGUCCAUCUUGUGUUGGUACAUUGGCAGAGACAUAUGCUUUAAAAACUUAAAUAUUUCGGAGGCACAUGUUGGACUACUUUGUUUUAAUUAAACUGCUAGUAUUUCUUUGUCAAGGAUGUUUCUAGUUUUUUGCUUUAUUGCCUUGCAUUCUAAUGCAGUUUGUUCUGUAACUCGAGAGCCAGUAGCAUUGGAUUGAUGGAAGUGUAGGGUUUAUGAAUUAUUGCAGCUGACUACCAUACCUCACACAGCGUUGGUGUUGUGAGCGGCCCAUGAAAAGCCAAAUUAAAAAUCAAGGAUUCAGUCAAACUAAGCAGGUACUCAUGCCAGGUACUCCUUUCUCUACCCACAUCCAUGUUUGAAUGCUAUUGCCUGUGAUCUUUACGCUUAACUGUUGUGUAUCUUUUUUGUUCUUUACAAGAAGUGCAGAGGGGUUUUUUGUGUAUUGCGUGAAAACUUAUAAAACAAAUGUUAACAGAAUGGAAUUUUUUUUCAACUGUAUGUAGGGCUGCAGUGGUGGCCAGAAUUAGAUAUCUUUAAAGAAUUUUAAAUACAAUAAACACUUCAUAUUAUUCGCCUUGUUACACUCAAUGCAAUUCUCAAGUCUAUAAGAGGUAUGUGCUUAAUAUUUCCUACUGUGUAGGAGAAUUUGCAGUCAGCCAUAGGUAUGUAGGAAUAGUCACUCACUGGCUGAUACAUUUAAAGCAGCAGUGUGAAUAGCAAGGACAGACACCUUCAAUUUGUGAAAUCAAAGAACUGAUGCACUAUAUAGAACGAAUUUGGGUUUUUAAAGAAAUAUUAAAAGUUAGGUACUGUAAGUGUUCUUAAAACCUGUAAACUUCAUUCUGUGGGCUAGUGGUGUGGGACAAAAUAUUCCUAAUGAAAGGAAGUACCAAUUAGUUGAUUUGUUGGUGGCAUUCCCCUUUUGGGAAAGCAAUGUAAGGUUAUGUCUGUGUAUGUCAUUCACACUUAGGCAAGCAUACACAGGCACAUGGCUUUAAGAACCACACUGAUGCCUUGAUAAUUAAAAAGAAUACAAGCAUUCCAUGUACACAUGUUAAUUAGCAGUUAGUGACUGGGCCAACACUUUCUCAUAAAAAUUGGCCUUUUACAUGUUGUCUAAUUAUCAUUUUUCCCCAAAUUUUGCGUUGUAGGACUACUGUUCGAAGAUUUUUGGAAGAAUACUGAGAACGGCAUAAAGUGAAGAUCGACAUUUAAAAAAUGAGGUGAAAGAAAGCUAUAGUGGCAUAGAAAAAGUAUAAAGCUCAGUUAGUUUUUUUAUUAUUAUUAUUAUUAAAAGUUAAUUCAGGACUGAUGUGACCUACCAGAUUUCAGAACAUGUGUUAAUAGUAUAUAUGCCACUGAAAACUUAGGUCCUGUAUCAUACUUUUUUCUUUAAGACUUUUUAAGAAAUAUUACUUAAACAUGUGGCUUGCUCAGUGUUUAAUUGCAAGUUUUCAAUCUUGGACUUUGAAAACAGGAUUAAACGUUAGUAUUCGUGUGAAUCAGACUAAGUGGGAUUUCAUUUUUACAACUCUGCUCUACUUAGCCUUUGGAUUUAGAAGUAAAAAUAAAGUAUCUCUGACUUUCUGUUACAAAGUUGAUUGUCUCUGUCAUUGAAAAGUUUUAGUAUUAAUCUUUUUCUAAUAAAGUUAUUGACUCUGAACUAGUCCCCUGUUUUAAAUACAAGAGUUACACUAUUACUAGAGGUGUUGGUGUACAGUUUUAUCUGAUUUGUUCUGUUUAAGACUAAUUUUUAUAGACUUUCUAAUGUUUUAAAUAAUGGUGCUUCAAUUUUAGGUGGUUAUGAAUAAAUUUGAAUUUUGCUUUUAAUAGCAAAGAUGUGCAGUGAACUAGAAUAUAUUUUUACAUCCCUGAGAGAUUCAUUUAGUAGAAAAUUCCAAGUAUCCUGACAAGCACUCUUUAGCUGGCUAGCUAUGGGAUGAUGUAGAAAAGCAUUCAAGAGCUAGUUUUUGUUAAGUCCUGUAUCAAGAUUAACCCAGCUGUGUCAGUUUAUAAAUGUAUUUGUGUAUAGGGUGUGUAGUAUAUAUGGCAAGGGUUUUUUCCCCCCACUUAAGUGAUUAUUUUUGUGUCACAUCUAGGAAAACCGGCAGCAUGUUUCUAUCUAUAGCCAGCUUCUUCGACUGUAUAAAAGUAUUCUCUCCAGCUACGUAUAUACACACAUACAUAUAUAUCAUAGCAAUUCCUUGUGGUUUAUAACUUGCAAAUACUGCUAUCAGUUUAUAGGUAAAGAAACAGUGUGUUAAAUGACUUAUCCAGGGAGGGUCCUGUGGCUUCAUGUUUAUGGAGUUGCUAGGUCUCUGCCUCAUGGUCCAGUGCCUGUUAAGCCACUGUGUUCAUUCUAAUAGGCAUAAUGAAUUGUUAAAGAAUUUACUAAAAUCUCUUCCACCAAACUUUGAAAAAUAAUGAAGCCGCCCCCACUUUAGAGGCUCUGUAUGAAAAAAUGCUGUGGAGACAGAGCCCUCCUGGCUCCCUAGCUGAUCCUGGAGAUGCAGCAAUAGAUGAAUGGGUUAUCUCUGAAUUUGUAAGAGAUAAUUCACAUGAGGAUUAAGAUAAAAUGGGAAGUAAAAUCUAACAAACACAAAGAUAGCUCCCAGGCACUGCUUUGUGUAGUUUGACAGCAUUGUGGUUGUAGCAGCAAAGGACUUAAAGUGAUAGUUUUUAAACCAUAUUCUGUCCCUAAGUAAUAAAAAAUCUAGGAAGUUACUAAAAUACCAGAUUUGUUCUGCUCUGCCUCAUCUAGAAUCAACGUCUAACUAACUUAAAUGAAGUAUAAUAAAUGAGUUCAUAUGAAAAGGCUUCCUCUAUGGACACUUAGAUAUAUUGUAACUAUUGAAGUUACCUGGGAUGUGGGGGUGGUGGGAGGAGGACCUGCCUCCCCAGGACAUCUAUGACUAAGGCCUGGCUUUAGUUAUGGAGAGAGACGUAGAAGUUGAAUUUUACACCCAAAAUUGAUGUGACUGAAGAGGAACUGAUUGUUGCUAACCAGCUCACAAGAAUCCAGUAUUGAGACCAGUUCACUAGAAGAAACAAACAUUUCUGCCAUGCAGACCAAAAAGUUAUUAGUUGGUGAAUAUGUAUUUUCUCUUUGGAAGGUCUUUAAGGGGAGCAAACCAGUUUUAAUCAAUCAGAUUGCUUGGUAAGUUUGGAAUCUGCAAUCAGUUGGUCUUAAAAAAAAAAAAACUUUAUUUUGGAAAUUUAAAGACAUACACAAAAGAGGAACAAUAUAAUUAACCUCUGUUAACUCAUCACCAACAAGACUCAUGACCACUUUUAUACUUCAUGAGUGAUUGUAUUUGUAUCCACUGUUUUCUAUUAUUUUCGAGCAAGUCUCAGACACACCAUUUAAUCUGUAAAUAAUUCAGCAUGUAUCUCUAAAAGACAAAGACCUCUUAAAUAACAGUUCAUUAGUAUAAAACAAAUUGGGUAAACUUUUGUUGGUCAUCAAACUAUAUUAGCACUGGUCCAAUAGUUUAAUUUUCAUUGAGCCUUUCAAGAGGACCGACCAGUCUGCUGCUCAAGACAUCCUCUCCUCUGGAAUGUAGAGAUAAUACAUAUCAUGCUCCUUUUUGUUAAAACGUUUUUUUUUCCCCUUCAAACACAGUCCAUUCAUUUUUCAGUUUGGGUUGAAACAUCCUUUUCUUGAUCUUGAGCUUAUAAUAACCUAGUCAUAUUGCUCAGCUCAGAUAUUUUUACUCCCUCUCCUUAGGCAUUCUGGUUCCUUAAAUAUAGUUAGUGUCACAGAGGAUAAAUAACCAACCUUAUUUCUAAGGUCUGAGAACACUUGGACCACAUAUUGGUUGAGCUCAGCCACCUUCUGAUUAAAGUUUUCAGACUUGUAAGAACUGAAAAUUUUUAUGGUGGAAGUUCUCUGAGCCCUCAUCCAUUCUGUUUUUAAAAAUGCAUUGCAGAUGGGCUAUGUGAAUAUGUUUUUAAACAUCUGAUAUGUGCAUGAAACAAAAAACACUUGAAGUUAUUAUGUAUACAAUUCUGUGGGAUGGGACUUCAUGCAGGAUUGGUUUUCAAGUUUGAUUUCCUGAGGGAUUUUUUAGUUGUUUGUGAAAGAACCCCAGGUCUACUUUUGAAAUUUUGUAUUAUAAUUGUAAUGUUGCCCAUGGUUAAAAAAAAAAAGUGUUCAGUGAUCUAUGUCUCCUACUACUCCUAUUUCUCUGUUUUUCCUCUGCAGGAGCUUGCUGCUGUUAACAGUUAUUCUUCCAAGUUGUUUUCUUUGUGGGGAGAUGGGAGGUGGGAGGAAAUAUAAACAUAUAUGUAUAGAUCUUUCAAAAUAUAUGACGGUAUACCCGUAUGUUCUGAGUCUUGCUGUUUUUACCUGGUAAUAUUUAGAAACAUUUAUUUUGAGAUAAAGGAGAGCACUUUUAAGUUGAACCUGUAGUUUUAAAAAGUACAUUUCAAGUAAGCCAAAGCAGAGAAGUAAAUGUAUUUUUCAUUGUUGUAUCAGAAUUUUGAAUUUACUAUUUUAAAAAUUCAAGAGUUUUGUAGCUGAUCUAUUUCUUCCCCUCAGCCAUCCCAAAUAGGUCAUUUGUCAACAGAUUUAAGAAUGUUUAGAAACAACAACUUUGGGAAACGGGAAACAAUUUGGUAUAAGUGGGUGUGCCAUAACCUCUCUCGUAGCCAUUCAUUCCCGGAUACAUACCCUAGAGAAACUCUUACACAUGCGUACCAGGGGAUGGAUUUAAGCAUUUGUGUGUAAUAGGAAGAAAAGAAGAAAAAACCCGGGAAGAUCCCAAGUGUCCACCAACAGUGUGUUGGAUAAAUACUGUGGUAUAUUCCAACAGUGGAAUUCCACAGAAGUGAAACUGAACUGCAGCUGUGUAUGUGAACAUGGACAAAACUCAACAAUAGAAGGAUCAAAAAAAGCAAGUCACAGAAGAAUACAUCACUAUGGUUCCAUUUCAAUGAAAGUCAAAAACAGGCUGUCAAAUACAUGAUAAAAGGAAACGAUUAAGACAAAAUUUAAUGUUAGCCGUUUUGAUGGAGGGAGAGGUGAUCAUGAGGGCACAGGGGUCUUCAGAAGAACUGGUGAGGGUCUGUUUCUGAAGCCUGUGGGCAUUUCCUUUUUUAAUCUGUAUGUUUAUGUGCUUUUGUAUGUAUGAUAUUUCUUAAUAAAAUUUAAAAAGAAGAAUGGGAAAAAA